GACCCCCCCGUGGUGGCUCUGGGUGUCUGCGGAGGAGCUGGGGGCGGAAGCAUGAGGCUAACGGCUUGGCUUCAGUGAACGCACCGGGAUGUGCAGGCCGGGAGGUAGAGGCAGGCUGAUGGGGGAGGGAACGAGCAGCCUGUGAGACGGGGUGACGGCGGCUACCAGCCCGGGCGGGCACCGGGACUGGAAGAGUUGCCUGAGCAGCCGGCUGGUCCGGCGGCCAGGCUAGGGCGGGGGCGAGCGCCCAGUUGAGCCUGCUGGGGCUGGAGGAGCGAGAAGGGUUUUCUUCACAUUUCAGAGCGAACCAGACGGGGACAGUAAGGUUUGGAGGAAGGGGGAUCGUUGGAAGUAGCAAGAAGUGGAGAGAAUCUGGCAAUAGACGAGAAACCGAAAGAAUCAGAAAGAAGUCUAUGUGAGUAGCUGAAAGCAUUGGGUGACCAGAAAGAAGGUCGGUGUAAGUGAAGGAAGAGUGAGGUGUGGCUGGAUCAAAGGGCUAAGAGAAGCGGGUCUGUGUAAGUGGAUGUGAGUGAGGAUCAAGGAAAAGCCGUGGAAGUGGCCGGGGGUCGGGGCCGCAGAAGUGCCAGACGGGGCCGGAAAGCAGCCGAGCGGAGUUCAAAUUUGAGAGCGUUUGGAAAUUGGAAGACUUGGUGGCGAACGAGGGUCAGGACCUGCAUCCUGCCUCAGAGAGUUAUCGACGUAUCCGGAAUGUGGGAUCAGAGGCUGGUGAGGUUGGCCCUGUUGCAGCAUCUGCGGGCCUUCUAUGGUAUUAAGGUGAAGGGUGUCCGUGGGCAGUGCGAUCGCAGGAGACAUGAAACAGCAGCCACGGAAAUAGGGGGUAAAAUAUUUGGAGUACCUUUUAAUGCACUGCCCCAUUCUGCUGUACCAGAAUAUGGACACAUUCCAAGCUUUCUUGUCGAUGCUUGCACAUCUUUAGAAGACCAUAUUCAUACCGAAGGGCUUUUUCGGAAAUCAGGAUCUGUGAUUCGCCUAAAAGCACUAAAGAAUAAAGUGGAUCAUGGUGAAGGUUGCCUAUCUUCUGCACCUCCUUGUGAUAUUGCGGGACUUCUUAAGCAGUUUUUUAGGGAACUGCCAGAGCCCAUUCUCCCAGCUGAUUUGCAUGAAGCACUUUUGAAAGCUCAACAGUUAGGCACAGAGGAAAAGAAUAAAGCUACACUGUUGCUCUCCUGUCUUCUGGCUGACCACACAGUUCAUGUAUUAAGAUACUUCUUUAACUUUCUCAGGAAUGUUUCUCUUAGAUCCAGUGAGAAUAAGAUGGACAGCAGCAAUCUUGCAGUAAUAUUUGCACCGAAUCUUCUUCAGACAAGUGAAGGACAUGAAAAGAUGUCUUCUAACACAGAAAAGAAGCUACGAUUACAGGCUGCAGUAGUACAGACUCUUAUCGAUUAUGCAUCAGAUAUUGGGCGUGUACCAGAUUUUAUCCUGGAAAAGAUACCAGCCAUGUUGGGUAUUGAUGGUCUCUGUGCUACUCCAUCACUGGAAGGCUUUGAAGAAGGUGAAUAUGAAACUCCUGGUGAAUAUAAGAGAAAGAGAAGACAAAGUGUAGGAGAUUUUGUUAGUGGAGCACUAAAUAAAUUUAAACCUAACAGAACACCUUCUAUUACACCUCAAGAAGAAAGAAUUGCCCAGCUAUCUGAAUCACCAGUGAUUCUUACACCAAAUGCUAAGCGUACAUUGCCAGUAGAUUCUUCUCAUGGUUUCUCAAGUAAGAAAAGGAAGUCCAUCAAGCACAAUUUUAACUUUGAGCUGUUGCCAAGUAAUCUCUUCAAUAGCAGUUCUACACCGGUAUCAGUUCACAUCGAUACAAGCUCAGAAGGGUCAUCUCAGAGUUCACUCUCUCCUGUACUCAUUGGUGGAAACCAUUUGAUCACUGCAGGUGUGCCAAGGCGAAGUAAAAGAAUUGCAGGCAAAAAAGUUUGCAGAGUGGAAUCAGGAAAAGCAGGCUGCUUUUCUCCUAAAAUCAGCCAUAAAGAAAAGGUUCGAAGAUCUCUGCGUUUGAAAUUCAAUCUAGGGAAAAAUGGCAGAGAAGUAAAUGGAUGUUCUGGUGUCAAUAGAUAUGAAAGUGUUGGUUGGCGACUUGCAAAUCAACAAAGUUUAAAAAAUCGAAUUGAAUCUGUAAAAACAGGUUUGCUUUUUAGCCCAGAUGUUGAUGAAAAGUUACCAAAGAAAGGUUCAGAAAAGAUCAGUAAGUCUGAGGAAACCUUACUAACUCCAGAGCGACUAGUUGGAACAAAUUACCGGAUGUCUUGGACAGGACCUAAUAAUUCAAGUUUUCAAGAAGUAGAUGCAAAUGAAGCUUCUUCAAUGGUGGAAAAUCUUGAGGUAGAAAACUCUUUGGAGCCUGAUAUUAUGGUAGAAAAGUCACCUGCUACUUCAUGUGAACUCACCCCUUCCAAUUUAAACAAUAAGCAUAAUAGCAACAUAACAAGUAGCCCUCUUAGCGGGGAUGAAAAUAACAUGACCAAAGAGACUUUGGUGAAAGUUCAAAAAGCGUUUUCUGAAUCUGGAAGUAAUCUUCACGCAUUGAUGAAUCAGAGGCAGUCAUCAGUAACUAAUGUGGGGAAAGUAAAAUUAACUGAACCAUCUUAUUUAGAAGAUAGCCCAGAGGAAAAUCUAUUUGAAACUAAUGAUUUGACUAUAGUAGAAUCAAAGGAGAAAUAUGAACACCACACUGGUAAAGGUGAAAAAUGUUUUUCAGAGAGGGACUUUUCACCCCUUCAAACUCAAACAUUUAAUAGAGAAACAACUAUAAAAUGUUAUUCAACUCAGAUGAAGAUGGAACAUGAAAAAGACAUUCAUUCAAAUAUGCCAAAAGAUUAUUUAAGCAAGCAAGAAUUCUCCAGUGAUGAAGAAAUAAAGAAACAGCAGUCCCCAAAGGAUAAACUAAAUAAUAAAUUAAAAGAGAAUGAGAAUAUGAUGGAAGGUAACUUACCGAAGUGUGCAGCACAUAGCAAGGACGAGGCUAGAUCCUCUUUCUCACAGCAGAGUACAUGUGUUGUAACAAACUUGUCAAAACCUAGGCCUAUGAGAAUUGCUAAACAGCAGUCAUUGGAAACAUGUGAGAAAACAGUUUCUGAAAGUUCACAAAUGACAGAACAUAGAAAGGUUUCUGAUCACAUACAGUGGUUUAACAAGCUUUCUUUAAAUGAACCAAAUAGAAUAAAAGUCAAGUCACCUCUUAAGUUUCAGCGUACUCCUGUUCGUCAGUCCGUCAGAAGAAUUAAUUCUUUGUUGGAGUAUAGCAGACAACCUACAGGGCAUAAGUUGGCGAGUCUUGGUGAUACAGCUUCUCCUUUGGUCAAAUCAGUGAGCUGUGACGGUGCUCUUUCCUCUUGUAUAGAAAGUGCAUCAAAAGAUUCCUCUGUUUCAUGUAUCAAAUCAGGUCCUAAAGAACAGAAGUCCAUGUCAUGUGAAGAGUCAAAUAUUGGUGCAAUUUCAAAGUCAAGCAUGGAGUUACCCUCGAAAUCUUUCUUAAAGAUGAGGAAGCACCCAGAUUCAGUGAAUGCUUCUCUUAGGUCUACUACAGUUUAUAAACAGAAGAUCUUAUCUGAUGGCCAAGUUAAGGUUCCCUUGGAUGAUCUGACUAAUCAUGAUAUAGUAAAACCAGUUGUAAAUAACAACAUGGGCAUUUCUUCUGGGAUAAAUAACAGGGUCCUUAGGAGACCAUCAGAAAGAGGAAGGGCCUGGUACAAAGGUUCUCCAAAACAUCCUAUCGGAAAAACUCAAUUACUACCAACAAGUAAACCUGUAGAUUUGUAAUUGGUAAAUGUUAUACUUGUCAUUAAUGUAAAUAAAGUGAGUAAUUGGUAUGACUUGCAGGAUGAUGUACAUGUUAGUUUGUAGCUCAGGAUGAUUGUUAAGCAAUAGAUUUGCUCUAUUGAAAAUGUUUCAUUUUUUUCACUGUACAAGCAACUUAGAUUUUUAUUUGUACAAAUUACUUCUUUGUUUUUCUUAAUGAUGGCAAUUUUUAAACUUUAAUUUUAUUGUGAUCUCUUAAAGCAGAGGUUAGACUUUACCUUUCUGACUCUGUCGUCCAGGCUGGAGUGCAGUGGCGCAAUCUCACUGCAAGCUCCACUUCCUGGGUUCAUGCCAUUUUCCUGCCUCAGCCUCCCGAGUAGCUGGGACUACAGGUGCCCGCCACCACGCCCAGCUAAUUUUUUGUAUUUUUAGUAGAGACGGUUUCACCGUGUUAGCCAGGAUGGUCUCGAUCUCCUGACGUUGUGAUCCGCCCGCCUCAGCCUCCCAAAGUGCUGGGAUUACAGGCAUGAGCCACCACGCCCGGCUAGACUUUACCUUUCUAAAGAAAUUGUUUACUGGAUUUAUAAGAAGUUAAUUUUUGAAAAUGACAUAUUUUUGUGUGAUAGAAAGAAUGGAGCAAGUUGUGCCUAUUUCCUCCAAGUCAGAUAAGGUUUCUAAAAUAAAUAAAUUUCUAGCAUAUAAAGGGUAGAGAUAAACUCUGCAAAUCUUAUGUCUGGAAUUAUAUUAAUGUUUAUUGUCCUUGCCAAAAUUCCUAGAAAUUAAUUUCCUUCAAUAGCAUCCUAAAACUCUAUUUUUAUUUGGGGCAGAGUAAUUUCAUUUAUAGUGCCAGUAGGUGUACCUUGUGUUCACUCGAACUAAGAACAAUGGUUAAGGCAGAAUAAUGACUAAAAUAUGUUCAUAUAUUAUGAUGUGGAAAUAAUUGAUAACUUUUAAGCCAUACUAUGUUUUUAAAGAUAAUUUGCACAAACACGUUUGUGUCUGUUCUGUCCAAUAUAGAUUUGGCAAUUAUUUAAAGAGGGAUAAUCUUGAAAAAAAUUAACCAAGGUGAUUUCUUAUAUGUAGAUGCUCGAUUUUGGAAUUUGAAAUAGUAGAUGCACCUCUUUACCUUUUUUACUUGGAUAAAAACCUAUGAUGAUUUUGUCCUGUGUGUAAAUGUUAUUUAUUUAGCAUAGACAUUAAAGAUAACUCUCUGGAAAAUGACUUGACUAAGGCUCUCAUGAAAUUCAAAGUGCCAUUUAGAACAUGCACCAAAUUGUCAAGUAAAUCUGUCUAAAUUUAUAUUUUAAAUUAUUACAAAUUACACAUCUUUGAGGAAAGAGUAUUAUGAACAAUAGAACAUAUUCUCUAGGUUGUAGAGGAAGGAAUAAGCAGACAGAAUCAACCACUAAAGGUAGUUUUUCAGAUUGGUUGUUAGAAUGUCAUGUUUAGAUGUUGGAGCAGAUUAGAGCAGCAUUCAUGCCACUCGGAGCAACCAGACUUACAGCAUAAGUAUGUACGAGGAAUUUCAAAUCAUCAGAUGUUUGCUUGGCUAGGUUCUACUUUGUUUAUUUGAUAUCAAAUAGGUUUGUAGAUGUUUAUGGCAUUUCUAAUUGUAAGUAGAGACAAAAUAUUCAUAUAGUCAGAUAUAUGUUGUCUGCUUUAAACAAUUUUUAAAUUUUAAAAAUGCAUUAACGUCUUUUUAUAUCCAUCAAGGGAAGGAUGAAAUGUUGAAUUUGAAGACUAAUUCAGUAAGAAGUCCUAGGGGUUUAACUGUACAUACUACCUGAACUGGCUUUUCUGAGAGAUGAAUCAAUAAUGAAACAUGUCUGUUUUAAAAACUACCACAUGUGACUCCUAUUUUUGUUAGCUGAAAGCUGCUAUACGGAGUAUUACAGGAAUGUGAAGGUGACUAGCUUGAAGGUAGGGUAACUAGAGAGCCAGAAAAGUUUUGUUUUAAACUUGAUUUAAUGCGUUUUUAUUUUUUCUUAUACAAAAUAGAGAUAAUGUUGCUAACUUCAUGGAAUAUUUGAGGAAAUGAUAUGAAAGUGUCUGGACGUGCAGUAACCUCAUGGGUUCUUCUCACUGUCUUAUAAAUGUAAAUAAAGAUCUAAUAUUAA